CUCUCAGGCACACAACCCAGCACAGCAAGGCAGUCACACCAAGGCGGUCCCCAGCGCGCUGCCUCCGCCGUUCCCCGCCCCCUCGCCUCUGAGGCUGCCCGGAUAGCUGCCUGAUCCAAGGCCCAGCAGCUUCUGCCUUCCGGAUCCCCACCGACGGACGGAGGCAGCCCACCUGCAGGACCGGGGCGCUGUCGGUCCACGUGGCCGCUCUGGAGCAGGUUGGAGUUGGCAGCGGGCUGCGCUGCAGGGACAGGCGCGGCGGACAGCCCCGGGGGCAGCGGCGGGGUCCUGUCUGGGAGAGGACAGGGUUGCGGCGGGCGGAACGGUGUCUCCUUCACUUCGCCCUCCAGCUGCUGGAGCUGCAGCCCGACCGCGAGCGUGCCAAGCGGCUUCAGCAGCUAGCGGAGCGGUGGCGGCGGCCCCCCUCAGGACACCACCAGAUUCCCCUCUUCCCGCGGCCUCGCCAUGGCGACCCACGGACAGACUUGCGCGCGUCGAUCGGAUCAAUCACUUUUCUAGAGGAAGUAGCAGUCCCUCUUGUGAGAGCGCAAGGUCAUUACUUGUGCUCCUAAGGGCGUGGACGUGCUUUGUGGAAUGAAUGAGCUGGUGUAAUGAGCUCAGAUUGCCUGCCCUUAAGCAGCACAGCAUUGGCCGAGGACUUGAGAGUCACAUUACAAUGUGUAUUCCUCCAUCAUAUGCUGACCUUGGCAAAGCUGCCAGAGAUAUUUUCAACAAAGGAUUUGGUUUUGGGUUGGUGAAACUGGAUGUGAAAACAAAGUCUUGCAGUGGCGUGGAAUUUUCAACGUCCGGUUCAUCUAAUACAGACACUGGUAAAGUUACUGGGACCUUGGAGACCAAAUACAAGUGGUGUGAGUAUGGUCUGACUUUCACAGAAAAGUGGAACACUGAUAACACUCUGGGAACAGAAAUCGCAAUUGAAGACCAGAUUUGUCAAGGUUUGAAACUGACAUUUGAUACUACCUUCUCACCAAACACAGGAAAGAAAAGUGGUAAAAUCAAGUCUUCUUACAAGAGGGAGUGUAUAAACCUUGGUUGUGAUGUUGACUUUGAUUUUGCUGGACCUGCAAUCCAUGGUUCAGCUGUCUUUGGUUAUGAGGGCUGGCUUGCUGGCUACCAGAUGACCUUUGACAGUGCCAAAUCAAAGCUGACAAGGAAUAACUUUGCAGUGGGCUACAGGACUGGGGACUUCCAGCUACACACUAAUGUCAAUGAUGGGACAGAAUUUGGAGGAUCAAUUUAUCAGAAAGUUUGUGAAGAUCUUGACACUUCAGUAAACCUUGCUUGGACAUCAGGUACCAACUGCACUCGUUUUGGCAUUGCAGCUAAAUAUCAGUUGGAUCCCACUGCUUCCAUUUCUGCAAAAGUCAACAACUCUAGCUUAAUUGGAGUAGGCUAUACUCAGACUCUGAGGCCUGGUGUGAAGCUUACACUCUCUGCUCUGGUAGAUGGGAAGAGCAUUAAUGCUGGAGGCCACAAGGUUGGGCUCGCCCUGGAGUUGGAGGCUUAAUCCAGCUGAAAGAAACCUUUGGGAAUGGAUAUCAGAAGAUUUGGCCUUAAUAUAUUUCCAUUGUGACCAGCAGCAGGCUUUUUUCCCCCAAGAAGAUGAUCAAAACAAAGGAUGAUCUCAACAAGAGCUGUAUUUUAAGUAUUUAGACAGUUCUUUGUUAGCUGGUUUCUAGUUGGUUAUCUAGUUACCAAUGCUGCAGUCCUGCAGUCACCUAUACAUUAUUUAAAUGUAUUUAACUGUUAAAUGCGCUACCCACCAAUAAUGAAAUAGACCUUUAUGAAAACUGUGCAAUUGUGUGCAUGUUUGUUUUUAUGUUCCUUUAGAAAACAUUGACUGUUACCAUUGAAUGAGAUGGAUCAGUGGAUAUUAAGAUGAGGUUACAAAUUUUGUUAAGUUCAGCCAUUAUUACUUUUGGUAUCCCAGAACAUGACAAAUUAUGAAUAAAACAAGUAUACAUAA